GAGAAUUAUCGCGAUAGCAGCAGCGGCCGGGCAGGUAUUGGGGGCGUUCCGGAAUUGAGGGGUGGUUGUAGUGGUGGCUUAGGAAUACCCUCCCGGCUAUCGCUUCAGUGGGUAGAGGGGACCACUGCCCGAGAGCUUUAAUGGAGCUGGGUCCUGCCUUCGCGCUGAGGAGCCCUCGUUUUCGAGAUCAGGCCUGACCGGGAUAAGCUCCAGAAACAGUAUUAUGUCUCAGUCCUGUGCAAAGUGAGAUGAGCUGUAGCCUUUGGAGACCUAUAAUUUUGAACAUAGAUGUUCCUUAAAAGCUAAAUCUUUUUGAACAGAUGAUGAUAAACCUGGAAGGUUAUUUUGCCAUCCUUUCCUUCCAUGAUGUGAUUCUUCAGGCCAAGAAGAAAAAGAUGUGUCUGUAGCUAAAAUUACCUCAUCCUUGGUGUUUUUCAGCCUAGGAUCACUAUAUGUAGCUAAUGCCGUUACAUUACAACUAAGACAAGUUCCAAUACUUUUUUUUUUCUCCUCGAUCUGCAGAGAUUCACCAACAAUAGCAAAUUACACACUGGCUUGGAAAGUACUCCCAUGUUCCGUUUGAUCUUGGCAAUUUAAUGCUGUUCUUGAAGACUAAUUAGUUACACUGGAUAUGCUGCUGUUCUUUACUUUGGGAUUGCUUAUACAUUUUGUGUUCUUCGCCUCCAUCUUUGACAUUUAUUUUACAUCUCCUUUGGUUCAUGGAAUGACUCCUCAGUUUACACCAUUGCCUCCUCCAGCGAGAAGAUUAGUGUUGUUUGUUGCUGAUGGCCUUCGAGCAGAUGCACUUUACGAAUUAGAUGAAAAUGGAAACUCUAGAGCACCGUUUAUUAGGAAUAUCAUAAUGCAUGAAGGCAGCUGGGGCAUAUCUCAUACACGUGUGCCAACAGAAUCUCGGCCAGGUCAUGUAGCUCUGAUAGCUGGGUUUUAUGAAGAUGUCAGUGCAGUUGCCAAAGGAUGGAAGGAAAAUCCUGUAGAGUUUGAUUCUCUUUUUAAUGAAAGUAAAUACACAUGGAGCUGGGGAAGCCCAGAUAUCCUGCCUAUGUUUGCCAAAGGUGCUAGUGGAGACCACGUUUAUACAUAUAGUUAUGAUGCUAAAAGAGAGGAUUUUGGUGCUCAAGAUGCAACAAAACUGGAUACGUGGGUUUUUGAUAAUGUUAAGGACUUCUUUCAUCAUGCCAGAAACAACCAGUCUUUGUUUUCUAAAAUAAAUGAAGAGAAAAUAGUUUUUUUCUUACAUUUAUUAGGAAUAGAUACAAACGGACAUGCUCAUCGACCAUCCUCGAGAGACUACAAGCACAAUAUUAAAAAAGUUGAUGAUGGAGUUAAAGAAAUCGUGUCUAUGUUUAACCACUUCUAUGGAAAUGAUGGGAAAACAACAUUUAUCUUUACCUCUGACCAUGGAAUGACAGACUGGGGUUCCCAUGGGGCUGGUCAUCCUUCAGAGACUUUAACUCCUUUAGUCACUUGGGGAGCUGGAAUCAAGUAUCCCCAAAGAGUAUCAGCUCAGCAAUUUGAUGAUGCAUUUUUGAAAGAGUGGAGAUUGGAGAAUUGGAAGAGGCUAGAUGUCAAUCAGGCUGAUAUUGCACCAUUGAUGACUUCCCUUAUUGGAGUUCCCUUUCCUCUUAACUCAGUGGGAAUCCUUCCUGUGGAUUAUCUUAACAACACUGAUCUCUUCAAAGCAGAGAGCAUGUUUACAAAUGCAGUACAGAUUCUUGAACAGUUCAAGGUGAAAAUGACUCAGAAGAAAGAAGUUACUUUACCAUUUUUGUUUACACCAUUUAAACUGCUUUCUGAUUCCAAACAGUUCAACAUUUUAAGAAAAGCAAGAUCUUAUAUAAAACACAGAAAGUUUGAUGAAGUGGUCUCCCUUUGCAAGGAGCUAAUUCAUCUUGCAUUGAAAGGAUUGUCCUAUUAUCACACAUAUGACAGAUUCUUUUUGGGCGUCAAUGUUGUUAUUGGUUUUGUGGGAUGGAUAUCUUAUGCCUCUUUGUUGAUCAUCAAGUCUCAUUCCAACCUUAUAAAAGGUGUUAGUAAAGAAGUGAAGAAACCAAGCCAUCUCCUGCCUUGUAGUUUUGUAGCUAUUGGCAUUUUAGUAGCAUUUUUUCUGCUGAUUCAAGCCUGUCCCUGGACAUAUUAUGUAUAUGGUUUGUUGCCACUGCCAAUAUGGUAUGCGGUUCUAAGAGAAUUUCAAGUUAUUCAGGACCUUGUUGUAUCAGUGUUGACCUAUCCUCUGAGCCAUUUUGUUGGGUACCUGUUAGCCUUUACCCUGGGAAUUGAAGUAUUAGUUCUCAGUUUUUUCUACCGCUAUAUGCUUACCGCUGGACUUACUGCCUUUGCAGCUUGGCCAUUUCUCACUCGGCUGUGGACUCGAGCAAAGAUGACCUCACUGAGUUGGACUUUCUUCUCUUUGCUCCUGGCAGUGUUCCCACUGAUGCCGGUUGUAGGUCGAAAGCCAGACAUCUCUCUAGUGAUGGGUGCAGGCUUGCUGGUUCUUCUGUUAUCCCUGUGUGUUGUAACAUCUCUCAUGAAAAGAAAAGAUAGCUUUAUAAAGGAAGAGCUAUUGGUACAUCUGUUACAGGUGCUGAGCACAGUGCUCUCCAUGUAUGUUGUGUAUAGCACUCAGAGUAGUCUACUCAGGAAGCAAGGACUGCCUCUCAUGAAUCAAAUUAUUAGCUGGGCAACAUUAGCCUCUUCCUUGGUUGUGCCACUACUGAGUUCUCCAGUUCUCUUUCAGCGAUUGUUCAGCAUACUUCUUUCAUUGAUGUCAACCUACCUACUUCUAAGCACAGGGUAUGAAGCUCUCUUUCCACUAGUGUUGUCUUGUUUGAUGUUUGUCUGGAUAAACAUAGAACAAGAAACUCUACAACAAUCUGGUGUUUGCUGUAAACAAAAGCUCACCAGUAUCCAGUUCUCUUAUAAUACUGAUAUAACUCAGUUUCGACAGCUAUAUCUGGAUGACAUCCGUAGGGCCUUUUUCCUUGUUUUCUUCUUAGUGACAGCAUUUUUUGGAACUGGAAAUAUAGCUUCUAUUAACAGCUUUGAUCUUGCCUCUGUCUAUUGCUUUCUGACUGUGUUCAGUCCUUUUAUGAUGGGAGCCCUGAUGAUGUGGAAGAUUUUAAUCCCCUUUGUUCUUGUUAUGUGUGCUUUUGAAGCAGUUCAGUUGACUACUCAGUUAUCGUCAAAAAGCCUUUUUCUCAUUGUUCUCGUCAUAUCAGACAUUAUGGCUUUGCAUUUUUUCUUCUUGGUCAAGGAUUAUGGCAGCUGGCUUGAUAUUGGGACAAGGCAACUCCUGGCAUGUACUGCCUGGUUAUUUAUGUACAUAUCUGCCUCUCCCAAUAGACUGUGGAUGCUCUCAGAUCCAGGAUUGGAUUUGAAUCUCUUACAUGCCAUACGUGCUUGCAUCAGCCACUAUGUGAUUGUCAUGUCCAUGACCAUCUUUUUGGUGUUCCUCAAUGGCCUGGCCCAGCUGCUCACAACGAAGAAACUCAGACUAUGUGGCAAACCCAAAAGUCACUUCAUGUGAGGUUGCUGAAGCACCAUUCAGCAUCUGGAUCCUGAUUCUCCUUUUAAGCUAAAAUCUCAUCAAGGCUUCAAUAAGAAGAUGGAUAUGGAUAUAUAGUAUAUUCUACUCCUGUAAGGAAAAUGGUAUUUGGAAUUCCGAAUUGACAGGUUAUCUGGAACAAAGGAGCUUCUUUUUUUUUCUAGGUUUUGCAGGCAUGAAAUAGUGAUUAUAUCUGUGGAAAAGCAUAGGAAGGCAUUCUCCUUUUUCAUUUUUUUCCUUUGGCUGGCAGCUCUUCCCAGUGAUGUUGAGAGCACCUGCAGCAAUCUGGUCCCCAGUCGCACAACUUCCCACAUACCCAGAGGAGAGCAUAUGCCUGUGGGGGCAGUGCUGAUGGCAUCCAGAGUCAUUGCUGUGGCUGAGCUGGAAGGAAAUCACCAGGUGCCACCGUCAAUAUUUAUCAGCUUUCAGCACUGGUUUUGUUAGACAGUCAGGGUGUAUUAUUUCAAGAGCUUCAAUAAAAAAAGUGUUUGCAGGUAUUUGUCAUAUUUCUUUAGUAUGCAAUAAUGCUAUCUUAUCCUUUUUAGUGCUAUUUCUCAGGUUUUCUCAGUCAACCAGCUAGAUGCAUGUGAUGCAUGUCUAUCCUUCACUUUUUUUUUUUCAUUUCUGGAUUUUCCUGGGAUUUCUGACAACACAAAAGUAGAAAGUGCUUGGUAUUUCUGUCUUAUACAUAGGAAAACAUUUAAAAUAAAUAGUUUUUAAUUGUAGGCUCAACAUCUGUUACCCCAUAGCUUUUUCGUAUAUUGUUUCUUUCCCUUUGAAUUUCUUUUUACUGUCAUCUAUUAUUUUAACAGGAGUUAAAAUAACUCCUGUUAAACUUUCUGACAAUAUCAUAAGAAUUCAUAUUAAAGGUGUUAUUCUUUCUGGUUGUGAGAUUCUAGCACAAAGGCCUAAAAUCAUCAAAUUAGAUUUCCAUUUGUAAACAAAUUCUAAUGGGCAAAAUAUCUUGAGAGCAGUUUUUAUAUGGAUUAUCCAUAAAAUGACCUUUACAUAUCCCUGCAGAGUUGGCCUUUUGCCCGUGGUGUGCUAGUAGCUUUGGCUGAUGCUAAGCUUUCCUGGUAUGCGCCCUAUUUUUAAGAAGUAAUUGCUUUUGAAUUAAGUUAUAGCAUUACUAAUUCAUGUUAAUGACUAGGAAACCCUCUGUAAUUUACAAGAUUUUUCAAAUUGGUGGGGAGUGAAUAAAUACAAUUUAAAAGUCAGAAAUCAGUUUGGCAAAGUGUACUUUCUUAAUUUCUAUUUAUGAUGAAGUAUAGUCAUAAUUUAUUUGUAAUACUACUUUAUGGUAUACCAGUGAAAGAACUGUAGUAUAAAAAAGAGGUAUUAAUGUUUUAUGAAAUCUCAUGCAUCAGUUCAUAGCAUAAAAUCUAGCUGGACAACUAAGAAGCUAUGGUAGCAAACAGUGAUGUUGAUGGAAUGAGAAUCAUGAACUUUCAUAUUACCUCAAAGGAUUUUUUUAUCAGUUUUUUUCACACAUCAGAAAAAACUGACUGUAUAAACACUUAUCACUGACCUUUUUCUAUGUGUAGUUUUGCCUUUUAUCUUUUCCCAAAUUUUUAUAAAGAGAAAUUAAUAAAUAUUUUAUUACAACAUUGUAAAGGGUGCUCAGUUUUUUUAUCUUUCUUUAUUUUGCUCUUUGAGGCAUAUCUUUUUCUUAAUUUUGUCCUUUCAGGUCAGUGUGAGUCUGUAGAAUAGGUUGAACUUCCUUCUGACAGUAUCAUAGAGUUUGUGGAGUUUGUGUUGUGUGCCUGCAGCCACAGGCUCGCCUUGCUGCACCGUAACUGGCCCCUUCAGACUCACAUGGGAACAAGCCUUUUCUGUUGCAGUUUCCCAGAUAUCUUUAAAUGUUUUGAAAUGUAUAUUUUUAUGUUGCAAAACAGAAAAAAGAAACGAGUUAGGGAAAAAGUAUUUCUAUUUAAGGUAUUUAUUUUUUCAUUCUACCUAUGCCAUAGAUUUCUGAAUCAAGACUUAGGACAUUUGCUGAUUAACAAUGUUUAAAUUAGGAAUUGUUAUAAGAAUUAAAAUAGGCAGAACAAGUUGUGAAAAUAUUGAACCAAAAAAAGGCCAUGCUAUCAUCUUAGAGGGCCCAUGAAUAAACCUUAGAGGGAAUCCUAAGGCUUUAGGAAACCGCUGCAGCUUGUCUGUCAUUUUCCAAUAUGUUAAUUAUUAUACUUAGUGUACAGUAUUUAGAAUACAAAAUGCUUUUUUAUUUUUUAGGAAAAUAAUGUUAUAAAUGAUUGUAUAUUUUCAUAGUAAUGUCUUUAUAAUUAUUUAUUAAUGAUAGAGCUGAAUUAGAAAAGCUCUUCAUCCAUUAUAAUAUGGUUUCUCAUGAAAAACUUAUUACAAAUUUCAGCCAACUCAGAUAUUAAGAACAUCAGUGUCAAUCCUCCUCCCCUCCUGCGACCUUUUUACACUUGUUUUGGUGGACUAGGGGCUCCUUUUCUCCUCCUUUUUGACAUAUAACUGUGCCAUUAAAAACAUGAUUUCUGAUGAAGCUGGCCUAGAGGGAAUGAAGGAGAUUGCGUGGGUAUGGUCUCUAGGACAGGCGUAGCUGUUGCAGGGCCACCCUGUCCUUGGGAGAACCUGGUGAGCUCCCAUAUUCACACUAGAUGCCAUCAUGUCAGGGGGCUGAAGAGAAUGGAGCUAAUCAACUCUGUCAUUUGGAGAAGACCCCCUUCAGACCAGUUCUGAGAACUCCUUCUUUUAAGAGACCAGAGAUAACUUGAUCAUUUCUCACCUUUUCGUAGUUGUUCUUUUUUAUGUUGACAUUCCCCUUACUGUUUUUAAAAUGCUUCAAAGCAUUAAUGAUUGUUAUGCUGUGUGCUUUCAGUACUAUGGCAAUAUCUUUGUAGCAUUUUCCCAUUUCUGUAUAAGCAUGGUUUUUUGUUUUUUUUUUUUUCGUUUUUGUUUUGAGACAGGGUCUCACUCUUGUUCAGGCUAGAAUGCAGUGGCACCAUCUCAGCUCACUGCAACCUCUGCCUCCUGGGCUCAAGUGAUCCUGCCACCUCAGCCUCCUGAGUAGCUGAGACUACAGGCACAUGCCCCCACACCUAGCUAAUUUUAAAAUAUUUUUUGAUGGAGACAGGGUUUCACUAUGUUUUCCAGGCAGCAGCAUUUUUUUUUGACUGGGAUUUCUUUAUGAUGCUUUGUUAUUUAAAAAAAAAAUGAGAAGGAAACAUUAAUAAUCAAAAUUAUCUUUAAUUGGCCUCACAGGGCUAAAAUCUAGAAUUAUUAUUACUCUUGGGUAAACUCAUGAAAAGUACUUAAUAUUCAUUCUAUAAAGAAACAAAAAGAACCUUUGAGAUGUGUCUCUUAUUCAUUUCCUUGGGUACACUUAAAACGGGUUACAGUUACUGCUCAACUUUCUACCUUCAGAACUGCAGCAUUUAUUUGCCACACAGCAGCAUUUAUCAGAGAUUGUCCCUUAGAACAUUGGUUCCUUGUAAUACAAAUAAAUGUCAUAAUAAAAAUAGUUUCUUUUUUCUUUCUUUCUUUUUUUUUCAAGACAGACUCUGGCUCUCUCGCCAAGGCUGGAAUGCAGUGGCGCAAUGUCAGCUCACUGCAAGCUCCGCCUCCCUGGUUCAAGCGAUUCUUCUGCCUCAGCCUCCUGAGUAGCUGGGAUUACAGGUGCCCACCACCACGUCUGGCUAAUUUUCAUAUUUUUAGUACUGACAAGGUUUCACCAUGUUUGUCAGGCUCAUCUUGAACUCCUGACCUCAAGCAGUUCACCCGCCUCGGCCUCCCAAAGUGCUGGGAUUACAGGCGUGAGCUGCCUCACCCAGCUGAAAAGAGUUUCUUAAUUAAAUAUAUUUGAGAAACAUCUAGUCAAACCACCUUAAAUAGGUAUAUUUACAUUAGUUCUAAGGGAAUUUAACUUGUGAUGUACGUUGUGAAGGGAGGAAGAUAGCAUUAUGCCAAAAGUUUCCACUAGCUUGACAGCAGACCCUGUCUUAGAGUUUUCUUCCUGAUUGGUAAACAUAAGAAAUGUUUCCAAAGCCGGGCUUGGUGGCUCACCCCUGUAAUUCCAGCACUUUGGGAGGCCGAGGUGGGUGGAUCACUUGAGGUCAGGAGUUCGAGACCAGUCUGGCCAAGAUGGCAAAACCCCAUCUCUACUAAACACACACACACACACACACACACACACACACACACACACACACACACACACACACACACACACACCCGGCGGGGUGGUAGGCUCCUGUAAUCCUUGCUACUCAGGAGCCUGAGGCAUGAGAAUUGCUUGAACCUGGGAGGUGGAAUUUGCAAUGAGCCGAGAUGGUGCCACUCUGGGCGACAAAGUGAGACUCUGCCUCAAAAAGAAAUGUCUCCAUAUAAUUUUGCACUAAAACCUUAAUUUGUCAUAGUUUUGAAAAUAGGGUGUUGUAUGUUGAUUGAAUUUUUUUCCCUGAGAACUGGAAUACCAUUUUUACUUUAACCCUUAAUGUGAGAAAACUUUACAAUUUCCUGCAAUUUUUCCUGCCUCUGUAUAUAUUACACCUGUCAUCAUUUAGUCUUUCAUGUGGGAAAGGCCAGUGGUACCAGAUUGCAUUCGGUUCAUCAUGGCUCAUUGUCUAGCCCUGCUAGAGUAUAGACUAAGCCUUCAUACCUUAUGUUUUAUAUCUUUUACCUGAAAAAUAAAUUUGCACCAAAUUUCAA